GGGAUUGGAGUGAAGAGGGUAUCUGCUUGACAGUGGAUCCCUGGGGAUCUACGCUGAGUUCGGAGAUGCUCCAGCUCGGGCCGCCCCUGUCUGAGCGGAGCUUUGCGGCGCUGAAGCUUACAGGGGAAGGAAAAGCCUCGCCCGGCGUCUGAUUGGCGGAACCGCGCUGCCGCAGCCUGGGAUUCCCCAGGGACCCCCCCGGAGCCGCCGCGUCUCCCAUGGACUUGCCCGGGGACUCCAGCCCGCCUGGCCAGCCGCGUCUGUGCCGCCAGCCUCUGACUCGAGCAUUAUGGGGAGCCAGGAGCCCGAAACGGCCGAGGCUGCAGCUCCCGGGGGCCCCUUCUCCCCUGGAAAAGGCCUCUCGGCGGGUCCUGGCCGUGGUGCUAGAAGAUGUCAUGGCUGUUCACAUGGUCCCCGUGGUGCCCUCAAAGCAGACCUCCAUACCACAGCACCACAGCUACCAUCAGGAUCCUGUCCACAGGCAGCCGCCUGCCUCGCCACCCCGGCAGGCCGGGUGGUCCUCGCAGGCCAGGCCUCCCGACCCUCUGUGUUUGUGUCGCGAGCCCUUGAGCCGCAUCCACCGGACCUCUUCCACCCUGAGGCGGCGAUCAAGGACAACCCCUGGCCCAGAGGAGGGCCCUUCACAAAAGGUGGACCGGGCCCCCCAGCCCACCCUGGUGGUGAUGCUGGAAGACAUCGCCAGUCCUAGACCCCCCGCUGAGGGCUUCAUUGAUGAGACCCCCAACUUCAUCAUCCCAGCACAAAGAGCUGAGCCCAUGAGGAUAGUUCGCCAGCCAACGCCUCCACCUGGGGACCUAGAACCCCCAUUCCAGCCAUCUGCUCUGCCUGCAGACCCUCUGGAGAGCCCACCAACAGCCCCAGAUCCUGCUCUGGAGCUCCCAUCCACCCCACCACCGUCCAGCCUUUUACGCCCCCGCCUCAGUCCCUGGGGCUUGGCCCCGCUCUUCCGUUCCGUCCGCUCCAAGCUGGAGAGCUUUGCUGACAUCUUCCUCACGCCCAACAAAACCCCACAGCCCCCACCCCCGUCCCCCCCAAUGAAGCUGGAGUUGAAGAUCGCCAUCUCAGAGGCCGAGCAGUCUGGGGCUGCUGAGGGCACUGCGUCUGUCAGCCCCCGGCCCCCAAUCCGCCAGUGGCGAACUCAGGACCACAAUACCCCAGCACUUCUCCCUAAGCCCUCUCUGGGCCGAAGCUACUCCUGCCCUGAUCUGGGGCCCCCUGGCCCAGGUACCUGCACCUGGCCACCUGCUCCACCCCAACCAAGCCGACCACGGCCGCGGCGGCACACUGUGGGUGGUGGGGAAAUGGCCCGAGCCCCGCCACCCCCUCGGCCCUGUCUCCGGAAAGAGGUCUUCCCUCUCGGAGGAGUGGGAGCCUCCCCUUCUCUCACCACAUCUUGCUCGUCCACGGCAUCCACUUCCUUCUCCGAACCAGCAGAACCCAGGUUGGGUUCAACCAAAGGGAAGGAGCCAAGAGCCUCAAAGGACCAGGUGCUUUCAGAACCUGAGACCAAGACCAUGGGAAAGGUUUCUCGAUUCAGAAUACGCAGAACACCAGCCCGUCCUCAGCUAAACCUUACACCAAUGGGACUGCCUCGACCAAUCAGGUUGAACAAGAAGGAGUUCAGCUUGGAAGAAAUUUACACCAACAAGAAUUACCAAUCACCCACAACCAGGAGGACCUUUGAGACCAUCUUUGAGGAACCCCGGGAGCGCAAUGGGACUCUGAUUUUCACCAGCUCAAGGAAGCUCCGGCGGGCUGUGGAAUUUCGGGACAGCAGCCUUCCUCGAUCACGAAGACCGUCCCGUGGGGUCCGGGCUGCAGGGGGCAGGACUGUUCCUCCCAAUGUGGCCCCCAGCCCUGAUGUGGGCCCCCUGCUCCAGCAGCGGCUGGAGGAGCUAGAUGCCUUGCUCCUGGAGGAAGAAACAGUAGAUCGGGAGCAGCCCCACUGGACCUAGGUGCCCCAUCUGUUGGUCAUCCAUCCUGAAGGGACAGGAAACCUCCCAGGCAGUUAUUUUUUUUUCUCUAUAUUUCUAGUAAAGUUUUCGAUAUGUUUCUGA